AGUGGGCGGCGUAGAGCACUGCAGCAGCAAUGACGGAGGGCACGUGAGUCCCCUCGCCCCGGGCUCCUGACGAAUGCGGGGUGGUCCUAGGUGCUGAGGAGAGCGCGACUGGGGCAGUGGGCCGGCGGCCGGCGUUGGGGCGGGGCCUGGGUCGCUGAUGGCCGGUGGUCCUCAGGUGUCUGCGGCGCCGAGGGGGCCCCUACAAGACCGAGCCCGCCACCGACCUCGGCCGCUGGCGACUCAACUGCGAGAGGGGCCGGCAGACGUGGACCUACCUGCAGGACGAGCGCGCCGGCCGCGAGCAGACCGGCCUGGAAGCCUACGCCCUGGGGCUGGACACCAAGAAUUACUUUAAGGACUUGCCCAAAGCCCACACCGCCUUUGAGGGGGCUCUGAACGGGAUGACAUUUUACGUGGGGCUGCAGGCUGAGGAUGGGCACUGGACGGGUGAUUAUGGUGGCCCACUUUUCCUCCUGCCAGGCCUCCUGAUCACUUGCCACGUGGCACGCAUCCCUCUGCCAGCCGGAUACAGAGAAGAGAUUGUGCGGUACCUGCGGUCAGUGCAGCUCCCUGACGGUGGCUGGGGCCUGCACAUUGAGGAUAAGUCCACCGUGUUUGGGACUGCGCUCAACUAUGUGUCUCUCAGAAUUCUGGGUGUUGGGCCUGACGAUCCUGACCUGGUACGAGCCCGGAACAUUCUUCACAAGAAAGGUGGUGCUGUGGCCAUCCCCUCCUGGGGGAAGUUCUGGCUGGCUGUCCUGAAUGUUUACAGCUGGGAAGGCCUCAAUACCCUGUUCCCAGAGAUGUGGCUGUUUCCUGACUGGGCACCGGCACACCCCUCCACACUCUGGUGCCACUGCCGGCAGGUGUACCUGCCCAUGAGCUACUGCUACGCCGUUCGGCUGAGUGCCGCGGAAGACCCGCUGGUCCAGAGCCUCCGCCAGGAGCUCUAUGUGGAGGACUUCGCCAGCAUUGACUGGCUGGCGCAGAGGAACAACGUGGCCCCCGACGAGCUGUACACGCCGCACAGCUGGCUGCUCCGCGUGGUAUAUGCGCUCCUCAACCUGUAUGAGCACCACCACAGUGCCCACCUGCGGCAGCGGGCCGUGCAGAAGCUGUAUGAACACAUUGUGGCCGACGACCGAUUCACCAAGAGCAUCAGCAUCGGCCCGAUCUCGAAAACCAUCAACAUGCUUGUGCGCUGGUAUGUGGACGGGCCCGCCUCCACUGCCUUCCAGGAGCAUGUCUCCAGAAUCCCGGACUAUCUCUGGAUGGGCCUUGACGGCAUGAAAAUGCAGGGCACCAACGGCUCACAGAUCUGGGACACCGCAUUCGCCAUCCAGGCUCUGCUUGAGGCGGGCGGGCACCACAGGCCCGAGUUUUCGUCCUGCCUGCAGAAGGCUCAUGAGUUCCUGAGGCUCUCACAGGUCCCAGAUAACCCUCCCGACUACCAGAAGUACUACCGCCAGAUGCGCAAGGGUGGCUUCUCCUUCAGUACGCUGGACUGCGGCUGGAUCGUUUCUGACUGCACGGCUGAGGCCUUGAAGGCUGUGCUGCUCCUGCAGGAGAAGUGUCCCCAUGUCACCGAGCACAUCCCCAGAGAACGGCUCUGCGAUGCUGUGGCUGUGCUGCUGAACAUGAGAAAUCCAGAUGGAGGGUUCGCCACCUAUGAGACCAAGCGUGGGGGGCACUUGCUGGAGCUGCUGAACCCCUCGGAGGUCUUCGGGGACAUCAUGAUUGACUACACCUAUGUGGAGUGCACCUCAGCCGUGAUGCAGGCGCUUAAGUAUUUCCACAAGCGUUUCCCGGAGCACAGGGCAGCGGAGAUCCGGGAGACCCUCACGCAGGGCUUAGAGUUCUGUCGGCGGCAGCAGAGGGCCGAUGGCUCCUGGGAAGGCUCCUGGGGAGUUUGCUUCACCUACGGCACCUGGUUUGGCCUGGAGGCCUUCGCCUGUAUGGGGCAGACCUACCGAGAUGGGACUGCCUGUGCAGAGGUCUCCCGGGCCUGUGACUUCCUGCUGUCCCGGCAGAUGGCAGACGGAGGCUGGGGGGAGGACUUUGAGUCCUGCGAGGAGCGGCGUUAUUUGCAGAGUGCCCAGUCCCAGAUCCAUAACACAUGCUGGGCCAUGAUGGGGCUGAUGGCCGUUCGGCAUCCUGACAUCGAGGCCCAGGAGAGAGGAGUCCGGUGUCUACUUGAGAAACAGCUCCCCAAUGGCGACUGGCCGCAGGAAAACAUUGCUGGGGUCUUCAACAAGUCCUGUGCCAUCUCCUACACGAGCUACAGGAACAUCUUCCCCAUCUGGGCCCUCGGCCGCUUCUCCCAGCUGUACCCUGAGAGAGCCCUUGCUGGCCACCCCUGAGAACAUGCCUACCUGCUGGGUGCCGUCUGUGCGUUCCAGUGAGGCCAAGGGGUCCUGGCCGGGUUGGGGAGCCCUCCCAUAACCCUGUCUUGGGCUCCAACCCCUCAACCUCUAUCUCAUAGAUGUGAAUCUGGGGGCCAGGCUGGAGGCAGGGAUGGGGACAGGGUGGGUGGCUUAGACUCUUGAUUUUUACUGUAGGUUCAUUUCUGAAAGUAGCUUGUCGGGCUUGGGUGAGGAAGGGGGCACAGGAGCCGUGACCCCUGAGGAGGCACAGCGCCUUCUGCCACCUCUGGGCACGGCCUCAAGGUAGUGAGGCUAGGAGGUUUUUUCUGACCAAUAGCUGAGUUCUUGGGAGAGGAGCAGCUGUGCCUGUGUGAUUCCUUAGUGUCGAGUGGGCUCUGGGCUGGGGUCGGCCCUGGGCAGGCUUCUCCUGCACCUUUUGUCUGCUGGGCUGAGGGACACGAGGGCAACCCUGUGACAAUGGCAGGUAGUGUGCAUCCGUGAAUAGCCCAGUGCGGGGGUUGCUCAUGGAGCAUCCUGAGGCCGUGCAGCAGGGAGCCCCAUGCCCCUGGGUCGUGAGCUUGCCUGCGUAUGGGGUGGUGUCAUGGAGCCUCAUGCCCCUGGGUCGUGAGCUCGCCUGAGUAUGGGGUGGUGUCAUGGAGCCGCAUACCCCUGGGUUGUGAGCUCGCCUGCAUAUGCAGGGUCUGUCAUGGAACAUCCCAAGUCUGUGCAGCAGGGAGCCCCAUGCCCCUGGGACAUGAACCCACCUGCGUGGAAUGCUGUUUGUGAGGUGUCUACAGGGUUUAUAGUAGUCUUGUGGACACAGAAAUGCACAGGGGACACUUACGGACACAGAAAUGCACAGGGGAGGCCGAGCAUAACCAGGGGUGAGGGGCAGGCAGCAGUUGUAGUUACUGCCGCGGGGCACUGCUAUGUGCAGGGACAGCCAGCACCCAGCCCAUCACCACUCCCUGGGCUGGCUGGCAGGUAUGGCACCCUGGGAGCCCGGCAUAUACCCAGGGCACCCCUACGGCUGCCGCCAGUCUCAUGCCCAGGUGGGUGCUCUGGGCUGGAGCGAGGGCCAGGUUUUGGGCCGAGGCUUCCCCAGGCAAUCCUGUGAGCUCCCUUCUAGCCUCUGACCCAGUCUGGUCUGGCUUGCAUGGAUGUAGGGCUUGGGGUGGGAAGUUCAGGUCCUGGCUUUGCCUUUGCCUGAUGUGGAUGAGCAGCUCACAUGCUCAGGGCCACCUGAGACUGUCACUGCUCUCCCCUGGCUACUGGGAGGAGUCACUGAGAGCUUCGUUACCCCUGCUGCCUUGCCCAGGGCACACCCUAUACCUCCUUAUCUGCUCUUCCCCUCCCUGCCGCCUUCUGGGCAGGUAGCAGUCCCUGGCCUCUCCCCCUGGCUGAUCACUCUCCCUCAGGCAGUGGAGAUCUGCGUCUGGACACCCUCAGAUCCUGUCAUUGCCUGCCCAGAGUCCUUCAGGGGCACCCCUCUGCCUUGGUGUGCAGUCCAGGGCUCUCACCCAGGUGCCGCACCCUCUGGGGUCUUCUGUCCAGCUCCCUUGCCCCAUGUGCUGUCACUGACUCUCCUUGGGACUCGCCUGCCUGCUCAGAGCCCUGCAGGGCUUGGUCAGCUGCCUGUUCAGUGUCAACACUUCCCUGCACAUCUUAAAACUGGGCUUUAUUUUCGCUGAAGGAACUGUGUUGGGACCCUUGACAUCUGUCAGGUUUGCACAUGCUGUUUUUUUUUCUCAGCCCACGUGUUCUCCCCCACGUGGGGUAGCAGCAGGACAGACAGUGAAUCACAGAGUCUGCCCUGAGCAGAGGCUGCUGUCCCUGGGACUCCUAGCCAUGGUCAGACUGUACAAAACGGUUUUCCAGAAAUGAAAUGUAAAUCCAUUUUUAUACUGAAAAUGUUACUGAAAGUCACUUUUAUGAGCAUCUGCCUUAAUAAACAGACAUUGAUUCCCUUAUCAGAAGCCUGUCACACUGUGUUUCGUUUCAUCCUGGGGAGAACUGCAGAUUUGGGGUUUCUGGCUGUCAUACGUCACCUGCCUGUGGGGCGAGUGGGAGGCCCAGCCUGGUUUAGGGAACAAGAGUGACGUGAGGAGUAGCAGGGUGCGUCUCCAGUUACCUGAGGGAAAACAGAUAUUUUAAGAGAUAAUAGCAUAGCCUAUUUUAAUAUGUUUUAAAGGCCAUAAGCAUAUCCAGGAAGAUAAAUAAACGUGAUACAAUGUCCACAUAGGAGGAACUUUCUUUCACUGCAUUGUUUUCCUUCACAGUGGCCUUCAAGUCACAGGACGCAGCGAUUCCCUGCCCUCUUCGGUGUUAUUACACAGGCAGGACUUCAGUGUCAGUAUCCCUGCCUUCAGUCUUCUUUAGAAAUCACAUCUGUGUUCAAUCCAUUGUUUAGAGGGAGUGUAUUUUUCCUGUUCCACGAAGAGGACUUUUUGUUCACAAUUGGAUCACAAUGCAGAGGAGUCUGUUCCUCCCCCGUCGGCUUCUCGGUGCUGGGAGGGUGACCUGUCCCAGAUGACUCAUCACCCUGACAUGCUCUUGACAAAGGACACCACCAAGAGGAGAUGGCAGCUGUACCGGUGCAGCCUCUGUCUGAGGGGGAUAUUUGCCUCAGUGUGAUUAAAAAUCAGUCAUGAAAGA